AAAGUUGAGAGAAAAGUCUUCACAGCGGAAGAAGAAAUCACUUUUUUGUCCCGAAUCAGUGGGUGGAGGCAAAACCCUUCAGCAAGAAGAGAAGCAACUUCAGCCGUGUAUGCAAAUGGAUAACCGGUUGCCUCCCAAAAAAGUUCCAGGUUUCUGUUCCUUUCGCUAUGGAUUGUCUUUCCUUGUGCACUGUUGUAAUGUUAUAAUAACAGCACAGCGUGCGUGCCUGAACCUCACAAUGGUAGUCAUGGUGAAUAGCACAGAUCCACAUGGUUUGCCCAACACCUCCACAAAGAAGCUCCUGGAUAAUAUAAAGAACCCUAUGUAUAAUUGGAGCCCAGAUAUCCAGGGAAUCAUCUUGAGUUCCACCUCCUAUGGUGUCAUCAUCAUCCAAGUUCCUGUUGGAUACUUCUCUGGAAUAUAUUCUACAAAGAAAAUGAUUGGCUUUGCAUUAUGCCUCAGCUCUGUGUUAAGCCUGCUCAUCCCACCAGCAGCUGGAAUUGGAGUAGCUUGGGUCGUUGUAUGUCGAGCAGUUCAGGGAGCAGCCCAGGGGAUAGUUGCAACAGCCCAGUUUGAAAUAUAUGUCAAAUGGGCUCCUCCCCUGGAACGAGGCCGACUUACUUCUAUGAGUACAUCAGGGUUUUUGCUGGGACCCUUUAUUGUCCUACUUGUGACUGGAGUUAUCUGUGAAUCUCUGGGCUGGCCCAUGGUCUUCUAUAUUUUUGGUGCUUGUGGCUGUGCCGUAUGUCUUCUCUGGUUCGUUCUGUUUUAUGAUGACCCCAAAGACCACCCAUGUAUAAGCAUCAGUGAAAAGGAAUACAUCACAUCCUCCCUGGUCCAGCAGGUCAGUUCAAGUAGACAAUCUCUGCCUAUCAAGGCUAUACUUAAGUCGCUUCCAGUCUGGGCUAUUUCCACUGGUAGUUUUACGUUUUUCUGGUCACAUAACAUCAUGACACUAUACACUCCAAUGUUUAUCAACUCCAUGCUUCAUGUUAAUAUAAAAGAGAAUGGGUUCUUGUCUUCCCUUCCCUAUUUGUUUGCCUGGAUCUGUGGUAACCUAGCAGGUCAGUUAUCAGACUUCUUCCUGACCAGGAAUAUUCUCAGCGUAAUUGCUGUCCGGAAACUCUUCACAGCAGCAGGAUUUCUCCUUCCUGCAAUCUUUGGUGUCUGCCUGCCUUACCUGAGUUCCACCUUCUACAGCAUUGUCAUUUUCCUAAUACUUGCUGGUGCAACAGGCAGCUUUUGCUUGGGUGGAGUGUUUAUAAAUGGCUUGGAUAUUGCUCCCAGAUAUUUUGGAUUUAUUAAAGCAUGUUCAACUUUAACUGGAAUGAUAGGAGGACUAAUUGCUUCCACUUUGACUGGAUUGAUCCUUAAGCAGGAUCCGGAAUCCGCCUGGUUUAAAACCUUCAUCCUGAUGGCAGCCAUUAAUGUGACUGGCCUAAUUUUCUACCUUAUAGUUGCUACAGCAGAAAUUCAGGACUGGGCUAAAGAAAAACAACACACACGUCUCUGAAGGUGAGAAGUGAUCAGAUUAAGGACAAUUUUUGAAACUGGGAAUGCAGGAGACAGAGGAGAUAAGGAUGACUCCUCAGACGAGAAGGAAUAACGGGUGCAGGUUUGGAGAAGAGGAGACCAUGUUAAGCCUGAGAAUAUUAGACAUCCUGAAAUGGCUGUGGGACUCUGUGGGGAUGCUAAGGCUGGAGAUAUAAAUUUGGGAGGCUGGGCCUCUUUAACAUCAAAAGAUGAGGAUGAAAAAGAGAAGUUUGCAAAAAAGACUGGGAAGGGCCUUCAACGAAGUAGGAAGAACAGUUGUAAAAUGGAGACUCGAAGUGAAAAAGGUUGGGAGCAAGGACCUUUGGCAAGUGCUAUAAUAUCAAGACAUUACAUUAUAUAAGGUCUAAGAAUUUACAAUGGUUUAGGCAAGAGAAACUUUAAAGGUAACCCUGACUAAAAUGAUUUUCAAAUGAAUGAUGGAGACAAAGAGUCCUUUAAGGUGUGUUCAAGGUAUAAUACUGUGCUUUGCUUAUGUAAACUCUAUCAGUGGUAAAUGAAUUGGAGGAGAAAUGUCUCUUUGUAGAAUAAUUUUGGCUAAUACAUAAAUAAGAAUUGAAAGAUGCAGAAUGUCCUUAUUUUGCAACCCUCAAUAAAUUAAGAGAUCCA